CUCGGAGCGACUGCAGCGGCGGCGGCGGACGCGGCCUGAGGCGAGCGGCGGGGCGUGGGGCGGUGCCUCGGCCCGGGCUCGCCCUCGCCGGCGGGAGCGUCCAUGGCCCCCGGGCGCCGGCGGGGCGCGGCCGCGGCCUGAGGGGCCAUGUCCGGGGUGGUGCGGACCCUCAGCCGCUGCCUGCUGCCGGCCGAGGCCGGCGGGGCCCGCGAGCGCAGGGCGGGCAGCGGCGCGCGCGACGCGGAGCGCGAGGCCCGGAGGCGUAGCCGCGACAUCGACGCGCUGCUGGCCCGCGAGCGGCGCGCGGUCCGGCGCCUGGUGAAGAUCCUGCUGCUGGGCGCGGGCGAGAGCGGCAAGUCCACGUUCCUCAAGCAGAUGCGCAUCAUCCACGGCCGCGAGUUCGACCAGAAGGCGCUGCUGGAGUUCCGCGACACCAUCUUCGACAACAUCCUCAAGGGCUCAAGGGUUCUUGUUGAUGCACGAGAUAAGCUUGGCAUUCCUUGGCAGUAUUCUGAAAAUGAGAAGCAUGGGAUGUUCCUGAUGGCCUUCGAGAACAAGGCGGGGCUGCCUGUGGAGCCGGCCACCUUCCAGCUGUACGUCCCGGCCCUGAGCGCACUCUGGAGGGAUUCUGGCAUCAGGGAGGCUUUCAGCCGGAGAAGCGAGUUUCAGCUGGGGGAGUCGGUGAAGUACUUCCUGGACAACUUGGACCGGAUCGGCCAGCUGAAUUACUUUCCUAGUAAGCAAGAUAUCCUGCUGGCUAGGAAAGCCACCAAGGGAAUUGUGGAGCAUGACUUCGUUAUUAAGAAGAUCCCCUUUAAGAUGGUGGAUGUGGGCGGCCAGCGGUCCCAGCGCCAGAAGUGGUUCCAGUGCUUCGACGGGAUCACGUCCAUCCUGUUCAUGGUCUCCUCCAGCGAGUACGACCAGGUCCUCAUGGAGGACAGGCGCACCAACCGGCUGGUGGAGUCCAUGAACAUCUUCGAGACCAUCGUCAACAACAAGCUCUUCUUCAACGUCUCCAUCAUUCUCUUCCUCAACAAGAUGGACCUCCUGGUGGAGAAGGUGAAGACCGUGAGCAUCAAGAAGCACUUCCCGGACUUCAGGGGCGACCCGCACAGGCUGGAGGACGUCCAGCGCUACCUGGUCCAGUGCUUCGACAGGAAGAGACGGAACCGCAGCAAGCCACUCUUCCACCACUUCACCACCGCCAUCGACACCGAGAACGUCCGCUUCGUGUUCCAUGCUGUGAAAGACACCAUCCUGCAGGAGAACCUGAAGGACAUCAUGCUGCAGUGAGCGAGGAAGCCCCGGGGUUUGUCGUCGUUGAGCAGCCCCCACGGCUGUCGGUCAGACUCUUGGGUGUGUGUUGUCUGUGUGGUCCUUGAGUGGGUUUCUCGGAUCCGUGCCCUGGAAUACCUGGCUCAGGAAUGCUGUCAGACCAGCCAGCCAGCGAGCUCUAGGCAAAAGGACAUGGAAACUGUCACGUUAGCUACUGAAUCCUGGGGGCGAGUGAAACUACUGAAAAUCCGAGUGAUGAUGUUGUGAAUACGGAACACCUAAUCACACAGCUUGCUUUGCUUUUACAGAAACGUUCCUCUUUUUCUGACGCAGUUUAAUUGAGGACCGUGUUGUGUGUGUAUGUGUGUACACACGCUCUGUCUUUAAUGACAGAAACACAAAAACCAGCUGGCCUUGCAGACGGCUUUUCUAACUCACAAGUCUUCCCUGAGACAGACUAACCUGAAAGCUUUGCCUAACAGUAGCUUGUAGAGAUCCAGUGCACGCCGAUGCUGCUAAACUCAGUGCCUGAGCCCGGCCCUGCAGCCCCAGCCGCAGUGUCUGAAGGCCACCUCCCAAAGGGAGCACGUUGCCUUUUCAAACUCCCGUGCCGAUUUCCUAAGAGCCCCUAGUCCAAGCCUCUCAGAUGAAGCUGAGGAGCCGUGCCUAGGAUCCCUUCCCAGCUCUGAGGACGGGCUGCAGAGCUCUGCAGGUGUGGAUUCACCUUACGCCCCUACAGCAGGCUCAGCCCUUCCCACCCUGCCCCAUGCCCAGCAGCACAACACGGAGUGAGACAGGAUGCCCACGGUGACUGCCGCUCCGUCCGUGCACACACAGCGGUGCUCUUCUCCCCUUAGCCACCCACUGCCCAACCCAACGGCAAAGACACAGAAACCAGGUCCCCUUGCAGACGGCUCUCCCAUCUUCCUGCAAGUCAUCUGCUCACACACAGUUGGCAGCACAUAGCGUUUCCUUCUUUCAGAAACAUUCCUCUUCUGGGGCUUCAGAAAGCUGGCAAGGCCACUAGCAGAGCUUUUGUUAAUGCCCCAGCUGCUUGGCGAGCUAACAGCUGACCUUUCGGGAAGCCCACAGACGCUGGAGGAAUCUUGAGUUUCUCCAAACUGCCGCUCCACCAGUGCCUUUGGACAGCCGUGCCUGUUCGCCGCUCUCCCUAAGUCUGAUUCUCAUCGAGGCCCCUCGCUUCUAUGACUGUGCUUGCAGAAGAGUAAACACUCUCGGAUGCCGCUGUCCUGGGGGAGCCCGCGGGAGCCUGUGAAUGUUGAUACGAGCUGGCCAGUCCUGGGCCCAGCUCACUUGUCCAGCUACCUGCCAGGUGGCUUUCACUGUGUUUAAAAUACAUUGCAUUCCAAGCUGGUCCCCUCUGUGUAUCACUCUACUGAGAAAUCCUGCCUAGUGUGUUUUGGGAUGUGUCCUAGCAUUUACAAGAAAAUGAAAAGCGUCCUCUUAAUUGGCACCCGAAUGUUGCUGUGGCUCAGUCACAUAUCCCAGGGCCCUCGUCCCGAGGCCGUGCUGCCCCGAGCCCCGAGCCCCUCUGCAGCUCACCCUUGGCUUGUUUUCCGCAAACCCGGUAAACGCAAGCCCUUGGGGCAGAUGCAGAAGCAGAAGAGGGAGGGGAAACCUGCCUCUGGGUCACCCUGUUAGCACAGCGUUCUCAUCGGGAGACAGCAUGGAACUCUCUCUCGCAGUGCUCGAGGCUGUGUGUCAGUGUUUGCUGGGCUUGUGGCUCCUUUUUUGGCUGGAUAAAGAAGUCGCUGUUUUUGUACUGCUUCUGUGGCUCUUCACAGACCUCACGGAUGUGACCGGAGAUGAGUGCCGAUGACCACGUUUUAAAGGAGAAAGAGAGCUCCUGGUGGGGCCCUCGGGGUGGUCUCAGGUCCCAUUUGCAGUCUGCAACAGUGACGCGCAGCCCGGUCCGGAGCGUGGUGAGCUUUGUUUGCCUUCUGGGUCAGCUUUCGCUGUGUCUCCUGUGUGUGUUAGAAUCCAGAGCCCAGAGGAAGUGCAAGCGGGUCCUCCGCCAACGGGGAGAGCCUCUUCGCGGCGCUGUUGGCGACAGCAGCGCUGUGAUUCGCGUAGCAGGGGAGUUGUUUGAAACACCUUCCUGAGUAGUCCGGCCUUGUCAAUGAGUGCUUGUUUUCCUUUAAACAGUCUGACAUAUUUACUCGUCACUUUCAAACCAGAAGCAUGAGAGGAAGGAGAUAUUGUGGGGUCCGUUUAACUCGAUAGAAAGCGCAGGGGGAUGGCCCCCGGCGCGGGCUCUUGACCCGCUCAGCGCUGACCCCACCGCCCUGGCCGAGGCACUUGGCCUUGCUGAGCUGGACUUCCUCCUCCUCCUCCUCAUGACCGGGGUGAAUUAGAACGUUUUUAAAGACACCCCCUUCCAAAUUCUGUAACACAUUGUAAUUGGAGAAGAAGGAAACUCUGCAAGGCUAAACUGUCAUUCACAACUUGGCUACACAUAGACUCUAGUCAGUUUUGUCUCCAGAACCUUAGGCUUUUGUAUUUUUUAAUUUUAAUUUCACUGUUAAUCCUUAUUGUCUUUUUUAUUAAGAUGUUGGAAAAGCAGGAGGUAGUUGUGCCUCAAUUAUUGCAAAAAUGUAACAAUAAAGUUCCUCAAAAUAAGAUCUGUUCCUCAUAGCUAUACUGUGUACACAUAAGACGCAUAUAGGGUUUUACUGAAAUCUAUUUUUAACUCUUAUGUUCGUAGAGAAAUUGUUUCAAGGAUUUUGAGUCAUAGGUCUGUAAUUUAUAGAGAUCUCUAGAAUUCUUAUUGUAAUUUUCCUACUUCUUUGAUAAAAGAAAAAUAAGUCAGAUUGUUAACUCCAAGAUUGAAAAAAAAAACUCUUGAAAGAAGAUUAUUAGUUGUAACUAAUUUAGGGGUUCUGGGCACAGACAUCUAACCUGGUAUUGUAAGGCAGAGGCUCCCAUUGGAAUGGUAGUGGUCCGGGUCAGUUGUUCAUGGUGUAAGCUUUGCACAGUGUAUUAACAUUGGGAGGGUCUGGCUUGAAAAUUUGGCCACCCUCAGCCUCUGAAUGUUUAUUAAAAUAAAUUUAGUCUUUCUUUGCUUAAUAUAAAA